GUGCAGGGUAGCCAGUGCCCCGGCCAGGAAUGGACAGCCUCCAGGACACAGUGGCCCUGGACCAUGGGGGCUGCUGCCCUGCCCUCAGCAGGCUGGUUCCCAGAGGCUUUGGGACUGAGAUGUGGACUCUCUUUGCCCUUUCUGGACCCCUGUUCCUGUUCCAGGUGCUGACUUUUAUGAUCUACAUCGUGAGCACUGUGUUCUGCGGGCACCUGGGCAAGGUGGAGCUGGCAUCGGUGACCCUCGCGGUGGCCUUUGUCAAUGUCUGCGGAGUUUCUGUAGGAGUUGGUUUGUCUUCGGCAUGUGACACCUUGAUGUCUCAGAGCUUCGGCAGCCCCAACAAGAAGCACGUGGGCGUGAUCCUGCAGCGGGGCGCGCUGGUCCUGCUCCUCUGCUGCCUCCCUUGCUGGGCGCUCUUCCUCAACACCCAGCACAUCCUGCUGCUCUUCCGGCAGGACCCGGACGUGUCCAGGUUGACCCAGGACUAUGUAAUGAUUUUCAUUCCAGGACUUCCGGUGAUUUUUCUUUACAAUCUGCUGGCAAAAUAUUUGCAAAAUCAGAAGAUCACCUGGCCCCAAGUCCUCAGUGGUGUGGUGGGCAACUGUGUCAACGGUGUGGCCAACUAUGCCCUGGUUUCUGUGCUGAACCUGGGGGUCAGGGGCUCCGCCUAUGCCAACAUCAUCUCCCAGUUUGCACAGACCGUCUUCCUCCUUCUCUACAUUGUGCUGAAGAAGCUGCACCUGGAGACGUGGGCAGGUUGGUCCAGCCAGUGCCUGCAGGACUGGGGCCCCUUCUUCUCCCUGGCUGUCCCCAGCAUGCUCAUGAUCUGUGUUGAGUGGUGGGCCUAUGAGAUCGGGAGCUUCCUCAUGGGGCUGCUCAGUGUGGUGGAUCUCUCUGCCCAGGCUGUCAUCUACGAGGUGGCCACUGUGACCUACAUGAUUCCCUUGGGGCUCAGCAUCGGGGUCUGUGUCCGAGUGGGGAUGGCUCUGGGGGCUGCGGAUACUGUGCAGGCCAAGCGCUCGGCCGUCUCGGGCGUGCUCAGCAUAGUUGGCAUUUCCCUGGUCCUGGGCACCCUGAUAAGCAUCCUGAAAAAUCAGCUGGGGCAUAUUUUUACCAAUGAUGAAGAUGUCAUUGCCCUGGUGAGCCAGGUCUUGCCGGUUUAUAGUGUCUUUCACGUGUUUGAGGCCAUCUGUUGACUUCCCUCUUCUUCUGCAAUUUACACGAGCUCAAAAGUGAAUGCAGAUUAGCAAAGAACUGAAAAAUUGCAGCAGUGUAAAGCCACAAAUCUUUUUCUUCCGGAUUCCUCAUGAGCUGGGACCAUGACAUUGACCUGUGCCCCAGGCUGGCCAGGAGCUGAAUGGCAACCAUAUCCUGUUGCCAGCACAGAGGGACAUUUCUACAAGGGAACGAGCCCACCCAGAACACAGAAGGAACUGGACUUUCUGCUCCUUUGAUCACUAAAGGACAGGUGUCAUUUAACACAGAUUUGAAUUAUGUAAUUUUUUUUUUUUUUUGAGACAGGGUCUCGCUUUGUCACCCAGGCUGGAGUGCAGCAGUGCGAUCAUGGCUCACUGCAGCCUCAACCUCCUGAGCUCAAGUGAUCCUCUCACCUCAGCCUCCUGAGUAGCUGGGACUACAGGUGCAUGCCACCACAUCCAGCUAAUUUUUAAAUUUUCGUAUUUUUUGUAGAGACAGGGUCACACUAUGAUAGGUGGAAUCCUCUCCUGGUGGGCCUUCCAACGUUGGCCUGAGUCACUAGCCUGGGCCAGAGGAAGGCUGGCAUGGUGGAGGCAUGGCUGGCCUCGGGAGCUGCCAGGUUUAUCUUCCAAGCCCUGGCUGGCCUUGAACUCCUGGGCUCAAGUGAUCCUCCCAUAUCAGCCUCCCAAAGUGCUGGGACAAUAGGCAUGAACUACUGUGCCCAGCUAUGAUUUUUUAAAAACACAAGAAAACAACAAAACCCAAAACACUAAACUCUUGCUUAAUAAGCAGAAUUUGAACUCAUAGCUCUCCUACUUUGCAUCUGGAGUUACGUGAAUUCUUCAGGAACACACCCCUUGCAUACAUUCCCAUAGCUCUGCAGAAGGAUAUGCCCUUACUUAGCAAUACUGGCGCAUUCCAGCCCUUUCCCUACCUGGGGAAAAAACACUUGCAUAAUAAUUACCAACUCAUUACAAAUCUACUGAAAGAAAUCAUAUUUAUGGAGGAUAUUUCCAAAGGCCUCUGUGUACUCCAUCCAGUUCGCUAACUAUUCUAGGAUUUAUUUUUGAAUAUAGCCGGGCAUUCAGAAAGCGACAAGCUCGGGCCACAUGUUCUUAGCCUCAGCAGAAAUUCCCUCUCUGGGCUGUGUUCUGGCAUCAUAUUUGUGGCCUUUAUCAAGGAACAUUAAAUGAAACUACUUUAUGGAGCCCAUUAUUGCUUUUGUCAUAGGAUACUAUUUUUUUUUUUUUUUUUUUUUGAGACAGAGUCUCAUUCUGUCGCCCAGGCUGGAGUGCAGUGGUGUGAUCUUGGUUCACUGCAACCUCCACCUCCUGGGUUCAAGUGAUUCUCAUGCCUCAGCCUCCCGAAUAGCUGGGAUUACAGGCAUGCACCCCCAUGCCUGGCUAAUUUUUGUAUUUUUAGUAGAGACAGGGUUUCACCAUGUUGGCCAGGCUAGUCUCAAACUCCUGACCUCAGGUGACCCACCCGCCUCGGCUUCCCAAAAUGCGCUGGGAUUACAGGUGUGAGCCACCGCACCUGGCCUGGAUACUGUUAAAAGACACUAUUCAUACUUUUUCUCUAGUGUCUGGGUGAGACCACACCUGAGAAAUCAUUCUUGAAAUUGAAAGCUAGGAAUAGCUUUGCUUUUUUUUUUUUUUUUUUGAGACAGGUCUCACUCUGUCACCCAGGCUGGAGUGCAGUGGUGCCAUCUCAGCUCACUGCAGCCUCGACCACCUGGGCCCAAGCAAUCCUCCUACCUCAGCCUCCUGAGUAGCUGGGACUACAGGUGUGCACUACCAUGCCUGGCUAAUUUUCUUUUUAAAGUUUUGUAGAGAUGGAAUCUUGCCAUGUUGUCCAGGCUAGUCUUGAGCUCCUGGGCUUAAGCAGUCCUCCUGCCUUGGCCCCCAAAGUGCUAGGAUUACAGGCAUAAGCCAUGGCACCUGGCCCAGCAUUUCUUAAGAAAUUAAGUAUGCCUCCCCUUCCAGGGGGCAGUAGUUCUCUAGUCACUUGGCUACCAAGAAACUCCGAGUCAGGUUUACAGAGAACAGUUACCAGGGCCUGAGGGCUUGUGUAUGUGCAGCCCAUCAUUUUUCCUCCUGGCUAGUCGGUUUUUUCUUAAUUUACAUUUUCCAUGAGCCUUAUUUUUAUAUUUUGUAAACUUUUAGUGAGUUAUAAUUUACAUAUGAUAAAAUUCAUAUAUAAGUAUACAACUCAGUGAUUUUAAAUGAAUUUGGAGUUAUGUAACCAUCACCACCAUCUAGUUUUCCAUCACCCCGCAGAAUUUCCUGGAGACUGUUUUGUAGUUAAUCCCUGCUCCCAUCUCCUGCCCUGGGCAAUCCACUGCAUUGCUUUCUGUCUGUAUGAACAAUUUCAUAUAAGUAGGGUCUUAUGAUAUGCAGUCCUGUGUCUGGCUGCUUCUCCUUAGCAUACUGUUUUUGAGGUUCAUCAAUGCUGCAGCAUGCGUCACUGCUUCAUUCCUUUUAUUACCGAGUAGUUCCAUUGUAUGGAAAUACUGCCUUUGUUUAUCCAUUCAUCAGUGGAUGGACAUUUGGGUUGUUUCUAGUUUUUGCUAUCAUCAAUAAUGCUGUUUAGAAUGUUCACGUGGAAGUCUUUGUGUGGAUUUGUUUUCAUUUCUUUUAGUAGAGUUCUGGGAGUUGAACUGUUAAGUCAAAUGAUAACUUUAUUUUUAGCUUUUUAAGAAACUGCCAGCCAGGUGCAGUAGAGCUCAUGCCAGCAUACCAGUGCUGGUAAUCCCAGCACUUUGGGAGGCUGAGGUGGGAGGAUCAUUUCAACCAAGGAGUUUGAGACCAGCCUGGGCAACAUAGGGAGACCCUAUCUCUACAAAAGUUUUUAAAAAUUAGCUGGGGGAGGGGGUCGGCGGGGAGGCGGGGUUGGCACACACCUAUAGUCUUCGCUACUUGGGAGGCUGAGGCAGGAGGAUUGCUUGAGCCCAACAGUCCAAGGCUAUAGUCAGCUAUGAUUAUACCACUGCACUCCAGCCUGGGCAACAGAGUGAGACCCCCAUCUCUAAAAAUAAAGUAAAAUAAAAAAUUUUAAAAAGUCA